GCAAGCUCGUGCCUGCGGGGGACCACUGGCACCUGAGUGACCUCGGCCAGCUGCAGUCCAGCUCCAGCUACCAGGUUUUGUAGCCGUGCCGUGGAGUGAGAGGCUCCUCCCUGUUGCUGGUGUUCCCCGUUCACUGGGGCGGGAGCCUCGUCUGCAGGCAGCCCUUCACGGCUCUCUGGGCCACUCGCCCUCUCCCUUCGUGUGUGGCAGGAUGGAGAAACCCAGCCAGGGUGUCAGGGGCUCAGGCUGCCCAGCAGGCCCUGUGUGGCUGUGGCUGUUCCACGCGGCCUCGUGUCGGCACCUGCUAGUCCAGGCUAGACCUCCCUGCCCUUGGAUAGACCGCUCUGUAGCCAGGGGUGUACAGUGCCUGUCAGGGUUGAGCUUAGUGAUCCUCUCUCAAACCACACCCCCACAUAAAGCCUCAUGCUCACCCGGGCUCCAGCCAGACACAUCCUGCCCCUGAGAGCCACGCCUCUACUCUCGGAGGAACGUCAGUGUCUAGAGUGUGGGGUUUGCCCUCCGUUGGCAGAAAGGUGAGGAGAAAGCUCCUCUUCUCUGGGCCCCUCCCUGCCUGUCCCUGGUAACGCCUCCUGGGUCCUGAGUUUGAGAAAGCAGAGCCUCGCCCCAGCAGGUACUCACAGCCAGAGUGCGGGGGCCCCAGCAGGUUCUCACAGCCAGCCGGUGAGUGCACCUCAGAGCACAGGGGCCCAGAGCCAGGCCACUCCUUCAGGGCCCCAGGUCGCUUGCUGCCAGUUUUGGCCUGUGAGCUCACUGGCCUCAGUGCCAGGUAAGGACAGCCACCUUCCUGGGAAGAAGAGGUGACCCCGGGUCUGGUGGAUUUCCCACAGGGGCCGUCAGAGGAUGUCCACAGAGGCAGAGCCCUUGGGGCCUGUGGGCUGGGUUGGGCUGGUGGAUGUGGGGCCUGGGACUUCUCCAGAAGCUUACUUCCUGCUGCAUGCUUUGCCGACUGUCCUUCCACCUCUAAGUGUCCAUCGUGCCUGUGGGGGCUGCUGCAGGCUCCUGCUCCGUCAGCCCACCUGCUGCUGCGCUGCUCUGGGAGCGAGCUCCCUCAUGGCAUCUGGAACGCUCUCCUGUCCUCCCUGUGCUCAGGGCUGGAGAGAGGGUGGCGGGGCUGCGGGCUCCCCGGGCCUUCUGGGCCCAGCCCUGCCACCUGGGCCCACCUCCUCUCACUGUCUCUGGCUCACGCUUCCCGGGCCUGGAGCUGGGACCUGCCCAUAGGCAUCUGAAGACACGUCAGCCUCAGCCGGGGGGAGCCCUUGCUUGACGCUCUCUGGCCUCCGGGCUGCCUCUCGCGCCCGCUCUGGGCCCGCUCUUCUUCUCAUGAUGUCUUUCCUUUCACCUCCUGCGUUGUCUGACAUCGUCGCUCUCUUCAUAAAUUGUAGCGUUUUAUGUUUUCGUUCAUAGGAGUGUUUUAUUUGAUUUUUCUUUAUUUUAAAUUAUUACAUUUAAGUUCUUUUUAUUUUAUGCUCUAGGUUUUGAAGUUUUUCUAAUUUCUUAAUUUUUUUGUUGUUUUUUGUUUUGUUUUGUUUUUGUUUUUAUGUACUGUAUUUUCAGUGUUUUAACCAAACAGUUGUGGCUACUCAUGGUGAGGAAUGACCGCUAAGAGUUUGGGUUCUUUCAGUGCAUUUGGAGGUCACUGCUACACGUUGAUGUUUAGGAGGUUGAGAGGUUUGCCUUUAGGUAAGUUGUGGCCAGGGGGAGUGUCCCAUGGGUAAGUGGUGGCCCUGUAGGGUGACGGAGAGCUAGGGGAGGCGCAAUCAGACUGCAGAAUUCCCCGCAGCCACCAUGAGGGUCAGGAGCAGGCCGGGGACCCAGCGUGGAGGAAGGUGGCCCAGAAGCGUUUGUCUGAUGUGCACAGCUACACCCUGCCUGGCCACAUGGGGUUCCCUGUUUUCUCUCUGCCGGGUGGUGGCAGAGUCGGUGAGACACCAGGUGCCUGUGACACAUUGGGUAGACAGGUUCUUUGAGAACGUCAGCACAGACUUCUUGCAUGAGCGGUACUCGCUUCCUCCAGCGUGGGGAGUGACAUGAAGAGCAAGGGUUUUCCUUUCAAACUGGGCAUAGCUGCAGAGCCACAGGCCGUCUCAGACAUUUCUACAAAGCCACUCCGGGAGGCGGGCUGCGCCCGUGUGAGGGCUCUCCCUCGGCACUGCUCAUCUUUUGGGGCUGGACAUGCAUGGCCUGGGCCGCUGGGACGCGGUGGGUGUGGAGCAGCAUCCCUGGCUUCCACCCACGAAAGCCAGGAGCACCCCCUUCAUUUGUGACCACAAAAAUGUCUCUGGACUUUGCAAGCAUCCCCUCGGGGCAGUCAGCCCAACUGAGAAUAGCUACUAUAGAGGAAGGUGUGUCAUUUUGAGAUUCCUUCUAGAGAAACUUAGGAGCCUGGUAGAUGAAGCAGAAAUGUGUCCUCUGAGUGAGUGGCCGUGUCCGGUACUGAGAGGCCCCGUGCCCUGAGUCUGGCGGUGACCAGAGAGGCUGGGCAGAGGCAGAGGUCAGCACUGGCCAUGACUUCUGGAAGUCCCGUCUGCCCUGGUCACUUAAAGGCCAGUAUAAGUCAGCUGUGGAGAGGGCUGGAUACCCCCUCGACAGCUCCUCCCUGGGUGAGAUCCUUAGCAUUAGAGUCCCCCACGGUGCGCCCUCUGAGAGACCACGGGAACCCACCCAGCGGCUGCCUGGGACAGGCACAGGAGCCACCUGGGUGCCUCUGAGGCCUUGCACUUUCCCACACCUCAAGGAGGGCCGGGGGCCACGGGCAAGCUCUGCCAUAGCGGGUGAUCAGGUCAGCUAAGACGAGAACGUUUGGGGCUCUUUUUCUCCAGCUGGUUCAGUAUCUUUGUUAGGAAAGACCAUUGGAAAGAAUGUUUGUUUCGCAUUCCGCAUUAGUCACAUAGAAUGCGCUCCUCCCUAGCGAGCUUCCUGAGGUAGACGGCUGGUUGCGGUUUCUCGUAAUCCGGGCUGCCCCCACCCUCCAGAAUGUCUUGGUGGCGUCCCUUUCUGUGAGCAGGGAUUGUGGUUUCUUUGCGCUUGCUCAUGUUCAGGGGUGAGCUCUGGUCCAGUCAAGCCACAGGGUCAGCACCUUCUGGUCACUCCCUGGCCCUGACCUGAGCCCGGGGAGGAACGUGGGGCAGGCGCGGGUGGGCCCAGCCUCGAGCUCUUCAGCACAGUGAUGGUGACGGGGCAGCGGUGGCGGCACAGCCAGCCCUUCUUGGGUCCCCAGUCAGAGCCCUCUGCCCUACCUGGGCUGGACUUGUUUCUGAACAGCCACAAGCUACAGGGGGCUGCCGCUGUGUCCCUGGCGAGGCACUGGCCCAUUACAAGCAAUCGUCUGGGGAGGGCACCAGUGGAAAGCCCCGUUCCAAGCCAUUUCAGGAGGGUGGCCCUGCUUCCGAGGAGCCGGAGUCAGUGGCCGGAUAAGCAGAGCCACUCGGGAGUGUGUCCACAGGAUGAAAUGUCCGAGUCAGGCCAGUCCUCGGCGGCCGCCACACCCAGCACCACAGGCACCAAGUCCAACACGCCCACAUCCUCCGUGCCCUCGGCCGCCGUCACACCCCUCAACGAGAGCCUGCAGCCCCUGGGGGACUAUGGCGUGGGCUCCAAGAACAGCAAGCGUGCCCGGGAGAAGCGCGACAGCCGCAACAUGGAAGUACAGGUCACCCAGGAGAUGCGCAACGUCAGUAUAGGCAUGGGCAGCAGUGACGAGUGGUCUGAUGUUCAAGACAUUAUUGACUCCACGCCAGAGCUGGACAUGUGUCCAGAGACCCGCCUGGACCGCACAGGAAGCAGCCCAACCCAGGGCAUCGUGAACAAAGCUUUCGGCAUCAACACCGACUCCCUGUACCAUGAGCUGUCGACGGCAGGGUCUGAGGUCAUCGGGGAUGUGGACGAAGGGGCCGACCUCCUAGGGGAGUUCUCAGUGCGCGAUGAUUUCUUUGGAAUGGGCAAAGAAGUGGGGAAUCUGCUACUGGAAAACUCACAGCUUCUGGAAACCAAAAACGCCUUGAAUGUGGUGAAGAAUGACCUGAUUGCCAAGGUCGACCAGCUGUCCGGGGAGCAGGAGGUGCUGAGGGGCGAGUUGGAGGCUGCUAAGCAGGCCAAAGUCAAGCUGGAAAACCGUAUCAAGGAGCUGGAAGAGGAACUGAAAAGAGUGAAGUCCGAGGCCAUCAUCGCCCGCCGUGAACCCAAAGAAGAGGCGGAGGAUGUAAGCAGCUAUCUCUGUACAGAAUCGGACAAAAUCCCCAUGGCCCAGCGCCGCCGCUUCACGCGGGUGGAGAUGGCCCGUGUGCUCAUGGAGCGGAACCAGUACAAGGAGCGGCUGAUGGAGCUGCAGGAGGCUGUGCGGUGGACUGAGAUGAUCAGAGCGUCCCGAGAGCACCCAUCCGUCCAGGAGAAGAAGAAGUCGACCAUCUGGCAGUUCUUCAGCCGCCUCUUCAGCUCUUCCUCCAGCCCCCCUCCGGCCAAGCGCCCCUAUCCCUCGGUGAACAUCCACUACAAGUCACCCACCACUGCCGGCUUCAGCCAGCGCCGCAACCAUGCCAUGUGCCCGAUCUCGGCAGGCAGCCGGCCCCUGGAAUUCUUCCCUGACGACGACUGCACGUCCUCCGCCCGUCGAGAGCAGAAGCGCGAGCAGUACCGCCAGGUGCGUGAGCACGUGCGUAACGACGACGGCCGUCUGCAGGCCUGCGGCUGGAGCCUGCCCGCCAAGUACAAGCAGCUGAGUCCCAACGGGGGCCAGGAGGACACGCGGAUGAAGAACGUGCCGGUGCCGGUGUACUGCCGCCCUCUGGUGGAGAAGGACCCCACCAUGAAGCUGUGGUGUGCCGCGGGCGUCAACCUGAGCGGGUGGAGGCCCAAUGAGGACGACGCUGGGAAUGGAGUCAAGCCAGCGCCAGGCCGCGAUCCCCUGACCUGCGACCGCGAAGGAGACGGCGAGCCCAAGAGCGCCCACACGUCUCCCGAGAAGAAGAAGGCCAAGGAGCUCCCUGAAAUGGACGCCACCUCCAGCCGGGUGUGGAUCCUGACCAGCACCCUGACCACCAGCAAGGUGGUGAUCAUCGACGCCAACCAGCCGGGCACGGUGGUGGACCAGUUCACCGUCUGCAACGCGCACGUGCUGUGCAUCUCCAGCAUCCCCGCGGCCAGCGACAGCGACUACCCUCCCGGGGAGAUGUUCCUGGACAGCGACGUGAACCCAGAGGACCCGGGCGCAGAUGGCGUGCUGGCCGGUAUCACCCUGGUGGGCUGUGCCACCCGCUGCAACGUGCCGCGGAGCAACUGCUCCUCCCGAGGGGACACCCCAGUGCUAGACAAGGGGCAGGGGGAGGUGGCCACCAUCGCCAACGGGAAGGUCAACCCGUCCCAGUCCACAGAGGAGGCCACAGAGGCCACGGAGGUGCCAGACCCUGGGCCCAGCGAGCCAGAGACAGCCACAUUGCGGCCCGGGCCUCUCACAGAGCACGUCUUCACUGACCCAGCCCCGACCCCGUCCUCUGGCCCCCAGCCUGGCAGCGAGAACGGGCCAGAGCCUGACAGCAGCAGCACACGGCCAGAGCCAGAGCCCAGCGGGGACCCCACGGGAGCAGGCAGCAGUGCUGCACCCACCAUGUGGCUGGGAGCCCAGAACGGCUGGCUCUAUGUGCACUCGGCUGUGGCCAACUGGAAGAAGUGCCUGCACUCCAUCAAGCUGAAGGAUUCUGUGCUGAGCCUGGUGCAUGUCAAAGGCCGUGUGCUGGUGGCUCUGGCGGACGGGACCCUGGCCAUCUUCCACCGUGGUGAAGAUGGCCAGUGGGAUCUGAGCAACUAUCACCUAAUGGACCUGGGCCACCCGCACCACUCCAUCCGCUGCAUGGCUGUUGUGUACGACCGCGUGUGGUGUGGCUACAAGAACAAGGUGCACGUCAUCCAGCCCAAGACCAUGCAGAUAGAGAAGUCAUUUGACGCCCACCCGCGGCGGGAGAGCCAGGUGCGGCAGCUGGCGUGGAUCGGCGAUGGCGUAUGGGUGUCCAUCCGCCUGGACUCCACCCUGAGGCUCUACCAUGCACACACGCACCAGCAUCUACAGGACGUGGACAUUGAGCCCUACGUCAGCAAGAUGCUAGGCACUGGCAAGCUGGGUUUCUCCUUCGUACGCAUCACGGCCCUGCUUGUCGCGGGCAGCCGGCUCUGGGUGGGCACCGGCAACGGAGUGGUCAUCUCCAUCCCCCUGACAGAGACUGUGGUCCUGCACCGAGGCCAGCUCCUGGGGCUCCGAGCCAAUAAGACAUCCCCCACCUCUGGGGAGGGCGCCCGUCCCGGGGGCAUCAUCCACGUGUAUGGCGAUGACAGCAGUGACAGGGCGGCCAGCAGCUUCAUCCCCUACUGCUCCAUGGCCCAGGCCCAGCUAUGCUUCCAUGGGCACCGCGAUGCCGUGAAGUUCUUUGUCUCGGUGCCAGGGAACGUGCUGGCCACCCUGAAUGGGAGUGUGCUGGACAGCCCAGCCGAGGGCCCUGGGCCAGCUGCCCCUGCCUCGGAGGUCGAGGGCCAGAAGCUGCGGAACGUGCUGGUGCUGAGCGGCGGGGAGGGCUACAUCGACUUCCGCAUUGGAGACGGAGAGGACGACGAGACGGAGGAGGGCGCAGGGGACAUGAGCCAGGUGAAGCCCGUGCUGUCCAAGGCAGAGCGCAGUCACAUCAUCGUGUGGCAGGUGUCCUACACCCCCGAGUGAAGCUGCUGCCCUGCCUGGCCCGACCUGUACAUAGGACCCCCGACCACCUGACCCCCGCCCGGCCCGCGGGGUAGCCAGCCAGGCGCCGCCGCCCCUCUUCUAACCUCUCAACCUGCAGCUUUCACCUGAGUCUGGCCCCUCCAGCGGGCAGGGAGUGCGGGGAUGCGGAUCAGCUGGGAGGAGGAGGGGAGGGGAACUUCCACCCGAGGGGAAGAUGCUCUCGGGACAGUUUCCCGGGCAGCUCCUGGCCAGCUUCCAGCCCAGAGUCCUCAAGUCCAGGGCACCUUGGGCCCAGCGCAGGCAGAAUCCGAGGUGGUCCUGGCUCUACCCUGGGCCUCCUACUCCCCAGCACCCCUGGAGGAGGCAGGGGCUCCCCGCCGCCGAGGCUGCCUGCCCUGGGCCCACCUCUGCAUGCUGCUCAUGGGGCCACCCUGCCUCCUGGGCCCUCACUCUGCCUAGGGGAGCUGGGCCAGGCACUAGCCUUUGCCCAGGGAGGUGGGCCUCAGGCUGCCCAGGUGCCUGCACCCCAGCCGGCCUUCUCUGGGGCCUCCCCGUCGUCAAGCCUCUAUCCUGUCUGUCCCCACCCCAGCUGUCCCCUGCCCAGGGAGCUGGCAUAAAAGCACGAGGCCCGGCUCCCUGGGGCAGCUGCUUGAGAACAGAGACUGCUACCCCAUCCUGCCCAUGCAGGCAGGCUCUUGCCAGCCCCGUUCUGACCCGUGUCCCCCCAGGCUCUGCCUGGGCAGAAGACUCACCUUGGAGGAGUGGGCCCUGGAGUCCUGUCCCUCCCAGAAGCCCCCAGGGUGGGAUUUCUCAGGCUGCCAGGGCAGGCCCAGGCCUCAGGAAGAAGGGGAGGCCCCUGGCCUCUCCGGGAUCAGUCCUAGGACACAGGCUCAGCCUCAGGUUGAUGGGGGAUGAUGUGCUCCCGGGGCCUGCCUCCUGCACGGGGCUCCACGGAGCCCAGCUCCCAGACACGCUACUAAGUGCCUAGGGUUGCCCGCUGUGGCCUGCUUCCAGGGAGCAACAGAGAGGCCACCAAGCAGAGGCCCGUGGGGCUGAGGAUGGAGCCGCCCCCAGCCGACUCCAAGCCCGCAGAGGGCAGACGCCACCCUGGACUGCUCUCCCUGCCCAGCUGGGCCUCUCUGGCCUAUUCCUACCUUCCAGGCCCACUGCACUCCUGUCUGGGAGGCCCUUAUGAGGGCAGCCCAGCCCCCGCACCCACCCCCAACCAGAGAAGCACAGAUCUUGGGGAGCUGCCCCACAAGCCCCGCUGGCCACCGAGGGCUGCAGCCGCUGCGCUGCCGGCUUCUCCCCACCACCCUGCCACCUCCACUGUGAUGUAUGUCCGCUCCCUCGUCUGUUCCCCCAGGAUCUCGAAGUGACUCCGGGCUGAGCAGUGGGGCGGCUGGGGGAGGGGUGACGAUUCUCCUCAGGCUUUGGCCCUGCAAGCAAACCCACAUAUCUGCUCUGUAUGUAAUAAAUGUCUUAACGUCGUAGCUGCCUGUUCCUGGGCCCAAAUCGAAACGAAAA